AGUGCGCGCCGGCCGGGCAACCCUAUGCUGGCGUAAUCGGGUUCCUCCGAGCCGCCGUAGGACUGGUUCCGGCGGGCUGGUGAGGAAUGGAGCCGGUAGGCUGCUGCGGCGAGUGCCGCGGCUCCUCCGUAGACCCGCGGAGCACCUUCGUGUUGAGUAACCUGGCGGAGGUGGUGGAGCGUGUGCUCACCUUCCUGCCCGCCAAGGCGUUGCUGCGGGUGGCCUGCGUGUGCCGCUUAUGGAGGGAGUGUGUGCGCAGAGUAUUGCGGACCCAUCGGAGCGUAACCUGGAUCUCCGCAGGCCUGGCGGAGGCCGGCCACCUGGAGGGGCAUUGCUUGGUUCGCGUGGUAGCAGAGGAGCUUGAGAAUGUUCGCAUCUUACCACAUACAGUUCUUUACAUGGCUGAUUCAGAAACUUUCAUUAGUCUGGAAGAGUGUCGUGGCCAUAAGAGAGCAAGGAAAAGAACUAGUAUGGAAACAGCACUUGCCCUUGAGAAGCUAUUCCCCAAACAAUGCCAAGUCCUUGGGAUUGUGACCCCAGGAAUUGUAGUGACUCCAAUGGGAUCAGGUAGCAAUCGACCUCAGGAAAUAGAAAUUGGAGAAUCUGGUUUUGCUUUAUUAUUCCCUCAAAUUGAAGGAAUAAAAAUACAACCCUUUCAUUUUAUUAAGGAUCCAAAGAAUUUAACAUUAGAAAGACAUCAACUCACUGAAGUAGGUCUUUUAGAUAACCCUGAACUUCGUGUGGUCCUUGUCUUUGGUUAUAAUUGCUGUAAGGUGGGAGCCAGUAAUUAUCUGCAGCAAGUAGUCAGCACUUUCAGUGAUAUGAAUAUCAUCUUGGCUGGAGGCCAGGUGGACAACCUGUCAUCACUGACUUCUGAAAAGAACCCUCUGGAUAUUGAUGCCUCGGGUGUGGUUGGACUGUCAUUUAGUGGACACCGAAUCCAGAGUGCCACUGUGCUCCUCAACGAGGACGUCAGUGAUGAGAAGACUGCUGAGGCUGCGAUGCAGCGCCUCAAAGCGGCCAACAUUCCAGAGCAUAACACCAUUGGCUUCAUGUUUGCAUGCGUUGGCAGGGGCUUUCAGUAUUACAGAGCCAAGGGGAAUGUUGAGGCUGAUGCAUUUAGAAAGUUUUUUCCUAGUGUUCCCUUAUUCGGCUUCUUUGGAAAUGGAGAAAUUGGAUGUGAUCGGAUAGUCACUGGGAACUUUAUAUUGAGGAAAUGUAAUGAGGUAAAAGAUGAUGAUCUGUUUCAUAGCUAUACAACAAUAAUGGCACUCAUACAUCUGGGGUCAUCUAAAUAAUAAUUAAAGUGGCUUUCAUAAUAUGUAACUUUUGGGUUCUGCCUUUUUCAGAAAAUGGAAACUUGGGCCAUGUGUAUUUCAAACAAAAAUAACUUUAGAUAUAUCUUUUUUGUAGCUUUGAUUGAUGCUCUAAGAUCACAUGAGGGUAGUAUUUAAUAUAUUAGAUGAAGGACAACUUUGGACAUAACACUGACUAGGAGUUGAGAGCUUUUGCAUCAGGCAGAAGCAAACUGAUUAUAGUUGUGUUGCACCAGAUCAUGUAGCUGCUGUGUAACAUGACCUUAAAUAGUCUUCCUGCAUAGGAAGAGCAAAAGGGUAUUCAUCAAUAGGAUAUAGAUUUAAGACAUUCCCUGACUACCCCUUGCGUUGUUAGGUGAUGUCUUUUAGCAGAAUCAUGAAGACCUUUUUUCUCCCUUAAUAAAGGAGAAAAAUAUACUGAUGGCUGGAGAAAUUUUUCUCUGCCUUUCAGUUUUAUGAAUUUUUUCAGAAGUAACAAUAUUAUUAUUGACUUUUUACUUAUUUGAUAAAAAUUAAAGAACUAUUUUUGUUUUGGUCAGAUAAAUUGACAAGACUAAUCAGUAUUUUAUUAUAAGUAAAAGAUUUUUCUUCUUUCCUUAAAAAUAUUUUUUUUUCACCUAGGUCUAAAUAGCUAACUAACUGGUAGACCAGAGUAUUACAUCAUCUUAUUUUGGUUUUAUACCAAUAAAACAUAGCGUGGAACUCAUUCAGGUAAUGUUUUGCAUUUCAUUGCUUUUGGAUGAACAAAGGAAGUAAACUAAUCCUUUAUAAAUGAAAACCCAGAAUAGUUGGUAUGUCAGCUAGUCAUUCCUGUCAUAUUCCCAGUAGAAUGAUUUUCAAGUUUGAAUUUCUGUACAAAUAUCUAAAUAAGAGAUGUGCAGAGAGCACCAAUUUUCCUUCAAUAUCCAUUCUUUACUUUUCACAUAAUGAUAGAACCUUUGAUUUUUCAAGUGGGUAUGCCUCCUAGAAUAAAGACUACAUUUCCCAGUCUCCUGUGCAGGUAUGACUGUGUUCUGGACAAUGGAAUGUGAGGGGAAACGAUUUUUUGUGUCCUUAAAAUGGCAUGACCAUUUAUUUGCCCCUUUCUCCAUCCUGUUGCUUGGAAUGUGGAUCUGGUAGUGAGCCAUCUUGGACCCUGAAGAGGAGGCAACACACCAUUGUAGAAGAAAAACAACAGAAGGAUCCUGGUCCCUGUACGACCUCAUUGAAGAAACACCAUAAGUGGCGUGGACUAUCUACCUCCAGACUGUUUUACAAGAGAGAAAUUAGCAUAUUCCAUCUAAUACAGUAUGAUGUAACUAAUGUUACUUUUGUAACAGUCAGUGGUUUGUUCUAACAGGACAGUAGAACACUUGCAAGGUAAGUAAAACCAAAUGUAUUAGCAUUAUUCCUGCUUUUCCUUUUUUGUCACUUUUAUCCUUUUUUUAAAACUGAAAAUAUUUUUCUCUUGCUAUUUAUAUAUAUAUGAUAAAAAUGCUUGGAAGAGUCCUUUAAUUUAUGGUUAUUCUAAAUCCUAGUUCCUGAGGCAAGUCCAAAGAAAAAUUUGUCAAAACUUUUCAUCUAUGAAUAUUUAUAUUUAGCUCUUGCUAUUUAGCUAUUAUCAAAAUACCUCAAAAUUUUAGUCCUUGAAUGUGCUCAUAUAGCCCAUAAGGCAAAUAUUUUUUAAACUUUAUUGUCCCUGAUAUUAACCAGAAUUGGUUGAAUAGUAGAGGAAAAGGGAUUUUUAAAACUGAAAAUAUGAACAAAAUGAGCCUUAGAAUUGAAUGGAUUAUUUUAAACAAAUUAAUACUCAUAUAAAAUGUUUUGCUGCUUCUCAAAGAGUCUGAUACAGGGUAAUUUCAUACAAUAUUUGAUGUUGUUAAAGCAUUCCUUUUUAUAGCUGAGCCUUUGGAGCUUGUUAUGAACAGUAAAAUCAUUUAGUCACAUGGUUGUAACCUUAGUGCAAAGUAAAAAGGGAAAAGUUGACCUAAUAGAAACAAUAGUAGUAUUGAUAAGAACAAAAGUCAUCCUCCCUGCCUCUCAGAGGCCCUGAAGUCCUGUGAGGAAGGGAAAUAGUAAUUUAACCAAAGUUAAAUCUGUGUAACUCAUUUAUUACAAUUUUGAAAGGCUUGUCUUAGAAGCAUUAAAGGAGUAUUAGCUAAAAACAAACUAAAUUCCUAGAGAUGACAAUCAUUGUAGUCCUCUGUGAAACUGAAAAUGAUCACAUGAAAAAAAUGUGAGCAUAAAAAAGAGAAGUAAAGGUGUACCAUUAGCCUACAUACUGAGCUGACGAUCAGAUCAUAGAAUACUUUAUUUAAUCAAGACAUUUAAAAAUACUUAUUUCAUCUACAUACUUUCAAAGCAAAAUAAUUUCUGGGGCUAGUUUCCUUUGUAUAAGGCUUAAGCAAGGAAUAUAUUUCCAUGCCCUUUGAUCCAAGUAAAAUCUAAGGAAGAGGGAAAGUAAACCUUGAAAUUAAGACCUAGAAAUAGAUCCACCCUUGCAGACUGAUAAAAGUGGGCAAUCUAGUAGGCCAGUUCACAUUACAGUUAUCUCAGUUUUGCUUAAAGCAAACCCUAACCCUCAACCUACGAGGCCAGAUAGCAAAAGACGUGCAACUGGUUUAUAUUGCAAAUUUAACAAAGUGAACAUGCAAAGAAUUACAAUAGAAAUAAACUUUUACAAAUCUGAGAACUUUCUUUUUUUUUGAGACGGAGUCCCGCUCUUUAGCCCAGGCCGGAUUGCAAUGGCACAAUCUUGGCUCACUGCAAGCUCCGCCUCCCAGGUUCACGCCAUUCUCCUGCCUCAGCCUCCCGAGUAGCUGGGACUACAGGCGCCCGCCACCGCGCCCGGCUAAUUUUUUGUAUUUUUAGUAGAGACGGGGUUUCACCGUGUUAGCCAAGAUGGUCUCGAUCUCCUGACCUUGUGAUCCGCCCGCCUCGGCCUCCCAAAGUGCUGGGAUUACAGGCAUGAGCCACUGCGCCCAGCCACAAAUCUGAGAACUUUCUAUGCAAUCUGCAGAAAUUUUUAAGAAUAUAAAUAUGCUUUUGUCAUUUUAUACCCAGUCUGGCCCAGGUUUGCACUGCCAUAAAUUCAGUUUUAAUGGGAACAGAAGACUCCAGAUCCUCUUGAUGGGAAGAAAUCAUGAAAUUUUAGAUGAUUGACUUGGUUUUCAUUUGUAGAAACUGGGUAUGAGUUGGCUUAAUGAAAAUCCUAAAAUAAUAAAAUAAGCAUUAGUAAUAAUAUCCUUGUUAAAUGAACAAAGUGAAUACGAUAUAAAGAAUGUGAUACCAGAAAGUUACUUUAAUAUUGACCCUAUAUAGGGAAGAAUAAUCAAAUAUUUGCAAAAUAUGUUAUUUUUGUUUUAUAUAUUUAACUUCUACCCUAUGCCACAACUGAAGACAGGUUACAAGAACAUGUGCUACUACAAAGUAGGAAACUGGCAGAAGCCAAUAAGUAUCACUUAAUAUUUUGGUAUGGAAACUUUUUUUUUUUUGAGAGAGUUUUGCUCUUGUUGCCCAGGCUGGAGUAUAAUGGCACAAUCUCGACUCAUUGCAACCUCCACCUCCUGGGUUCAAGUGAUUCUGCUGCCUCAGCCUCCCUAGUAGCUGGGAUUACAGGCAUGCGCCACCAUGCCUGGCUAAUUUUGUAUUUUUAGUAGAGAUGGGGUUUCUCUGUGUUGGUCAGGCUGGCCUCAGACUCCAACCUCAGGUGAUCUGCCUGCCUCAGCCUCCCAAAGUGCUGGGAUUACAGGCGUGAGCCACCGUGCCCAGCUGGAAACUUUCAUUUCUUAAAACAGAUUUAUAAAAGUUUUUGCUAUAUAGUGACUGUUAGCCAGUAAAAACAGGGAAGAUUGAUUAAUUUAGAAGAAAUUGAAAGAAAAUAUAUUUAUUAAUGUUGCUUUUAAAUGCAAAUUAUCAGAUUGAGGAGAAUUUUGAGACCAUUGACAUUUUUCUAAUUAUGACUAAAAUUUAAUCACUAUACUUAAUAAACAUACUCUAUUCAAGGUCUUGUAAUAAAAUUAUAGGGAGGAAUAAAACAUAAUUGACCCCAGCGACAUCAGCAAAAAUGGGUGGACUAGGAAGCUGCAAGCUUUUGUUUGCCUAUCAAAACAUUAAAAAAAAAAAAGAGGCCGGGCGUGGUGGCUCACGCCUGUAAUUCCAGCACUUUGGGAGGCCGAGAUGGGCAGAUCACGAGGUCAGGAGAUCGAGACCAUCCUGGCUAACACAGUGAAACCCCAUCUCUACUGAAAGUACACAAAAUUAGCUGGGCAUGGUGGCGGGCACCUGUAGUCCUAGCUACUUGGGAGGCUGAGGCAGGAGAAUGGUGUGAACCUGGGAGGUGGAGCUUGCAGUGAGCCGAGAUCGUGCCACUGCACUCCAGCCUGGGCAAUGGAGCAAGACUCUGUCUCAAAAAAAAAAAAAAAAAAAAAAAAGCAACUGUCUGAACGAACCUUGUUAGAGCUUUGGAAAACAGUCAAAGGUUUACAGCAACCAAAAGAAUGCCCAAUCAUCUGCAGAAUGGUAGGAAAAUAUUGUGACUUUUUAGUGGCUCUUGCCCGAGCCUCUCCCUACAUUGUGGCAGUCUUAAAGCAGCAGAAGCCCAGUCCCCUCCCUUGAACUGGAGAAAACAUGCUAGACCUUUUUUGCAAAUUACUGUGUACAUUUUUUUCUAACCUGUCUGCGGAUACUUGAAGGACUGACACAAGGUCACAUGUUUGUUUUGCCUAACUGGUAGGGUGGGCACUGCUUACAAAAGCUGCAAAGAACCACAGGUGCAUGGGGCAAGAGGUUAUGGGUGUAAACAUAAAAUAGAACAACUAAGGCCCAGAGGAGAAUCUGGGGUAAGACUUUGGGAAAUUAAGAACAGUUACAUAUACAGGGGGGAUUUAAAAUGCGACAUGCAUGCCCAGGGAAAACACUUGCCCGGAAAGUUCUAAGACCCAAGCUUUCACCUUGGUCUGGUCCCUAAGCCCAAAAGCAGGCCAAAGUAAGUAUUGAAGGAUUACCUGGGACAAAGCUGAUUUGUAAAAUCUAGGAUUGCUCCUAGCAUUCAAGGGAAUUUAUGUCAAAAUAGCUGAACGUGACAUAAAAGGAAGAGAGACUUCAGUGAUCACACACAGAAGGAAUAGUCUUUUAUAAAAAUAAUUUGGAAAACUCUCAAAACAAAUGGAUGACAGCUUUUAAAAAUAAAAAAACAAUGAACCAGAAAACCGUGGGGAAAGGAAAGAAUCUCAUACCUAGAGUUACCAUAUUAUAAUAGUGAAUAUCCAACUCUCAAGGAAAAAAAUCACAAACCAUACAAAGGAACAGGAAAAUAAUGCGCAUUCAAAAGAUCAAAAUUAAUUGACCUUGUCCUAAUGAAGGACAUUAAACUAGACAUAUACUUUAACUCAAAUAUGCCCAAAGAACUAAAGGAAAACAUGAACAAAGAAUUAAAGAAAUCAGGAAAAUGAUAAAUGAACAAAAUCAGAAUAUCAACAGAUAGGCAUUAUAAAAAAAUUCUGGCAGAGAAAAGUAUAAUAAAUGAAAUUUUCACUACAGGGGUUCAGCAGCAGAUAUAAGCAGGUAGAAGAAAGAAUCAGCAAACUUGAGAUGGGAUCACUGAAAGCAGAAACAACAAAUCAAGCCUACAUAGUUUUAAAAGAUACAUAUCACACACAAAGAAGUGAAGAAGAUAUGGUGCAUUUUUGAACCACAACAGGAUGUAGUUAGAAAUCAGUAACAAAAGGAAAAUUGGAAAAUUCACAAACUUGUGGAAAUUAAACAAAACACUCAACCAAUGGGUCAAAGAAGAAAUCACAAGGGAAAUUAAAAAGAGAAAAAUGCAACAUACCAAAAUUUAUAGGAUGCAGUGAAAGCACUGCUAAAAGGGAAAUUUGUAGACAUAAAUGCUUACAUUAAAAAACAAAAAAGACCUCAUGUCAACAACCUGACUUUGCAGCUUGAGGGGGAAAAACAUACUAAAUCCAAAGCUAGCAGAUGGAAGGAAAUAAUAAAGAUUAGAACAGAUAUAAUAAAUUGAAUAAAGAUUAGAAACACUAGAGAAAAAUCAGUGAAACUACAAGUUCUUUAAAAGACCAUAAAGUUGGAAAGCCUAUGCGUAGAUAGACUAAGAAAAAAAGGAAGACUCAAUUGCUAAAAUAAAUGAAAAUGGGAACAGCACUCUAGAUUCUAGAAAAAUGAAAAGGGUUAUAGAAGAAUACCUUCGACAAUCUAGAUGAAAUGCUCAAAGUCCUAGAAAUGCAAAACGUACUACUGCUGAACUAUGAAAAAAAUUUAAAAAUCUCAAUAGAACUAUAACCAGUAAGGUAAUUGAAUUAGUAAUCAAAAUUCUCCUGGAAAAAAAGCACUGGACCUGAUGGUUUUCAUUUGUGAAUUCUACCAAAUAAGAAGAAAUAACCCCAAUCCCUUCUAACUUUUCCCAAAAAUUGAAGAGGAAGGACGCUGCCUAAUUCAUUCUGAUGCUGAAGCCAGACAAAGAUACUACAAGAAAAGAUUACAGACCAGUUAUUCCUUAUGAUCGCUGAUUCAACAAUUGUCAAUACUAGGAAACUGAAUUUAGCAGCAUAUUAAAAGGAUUGUACACCACGACCAAAUGGAAUGAAUUCCUGGAAUGCAAGGAUUGUUCAACAUACAAAAAUCAAUAUAAUAUACUACAUUAACAGAACGAAGCGAGAACCAGAUGAUCAUCUCAAUUGAUGCAGACAAAGCAUUUGACAAAAUCCAGCAGCCUCUUGUGAUUAAAAACACUCAACAAAUGAGGGAUAAGAGGAAACUACCUGAACAUAAUAAAAGCCAGACAUGAAAAGCCCACGGUAGACACCAUACUUAGUGGUGAAAGCUUUUCCUCUAAGAUCAAGACAAUGCUCAUUUCACCAUUCCUAUUCAACACAGUACUAGGAGUUCUAGCCUGAGCUAGAAAAAGAAAAGACAUCUAAGUUGGAAAGUAAGAAGUAAAAUCCUAUAUGUUCACAAAUGAUAUGAUCUUUAGACAACCCGAAAGAUUCCACACCAAAAAAAAAAAAUAACUGUUAAUUCAGUAAGGUAGCAGGAUACAAAGUCAACCCACAAAAGUCAGUUGCAUUCCUAUACACUAACAAUGAACAACCUGAGAAGGAAAUUACAAGAACAGUCCCAUUUACCAUAGCGUCAAAAAGAAUAAAAUGCACAGAAAUUAGCUUACCCAAGGUGGUAAAUGGCUUGUACAAUGAAAACUACAAAACAUUGCUUCAAUAAAGAUAAAAAUAAACGGAAAUACAUCUCAUGUUCAUGGAUUGGAAAAUCUAAUGUUAAUAUGUCAGUACUACUCAAAGUGAUGUGCAGAUUCACUACAGUCUCUAUCAGAAUCCUAGGAUUUUUUUUUUUUUUUUUGCAGAAAUAGAAAAACCCAUCCUGAAUUUCAUGUGGAAUCUGAAGGGAUCCCAAAUAGCCAAGUCAGUCUUGAGAAAGAAGAACAAAUUGGAGGACUUAAACCUGCAGAGUUUAAAACUUACUAUAAUGCUACAGUAAUCAAAACAAUGUGAUUCUGGCAUAAAGGCAGACGGAUAGACCAAUGGGAUAGACUGGAGAACCUAGAAAUAAACCCUCUCAUAUGUAGGUAAAUGAUUUUUGACAAGGGUGCCAAGGCUAUUCCAAGGAUAGUUUUUUCAACAAAUAAUGAUGGGAAAGCUGGAUAACCACAUGGCUAACUAACAAAGUUGCAACCUCACUCAUUUGCAAAAAUUAACUCAAAAUGGACCAAAGACCUAAAUGUGAGAGCUAAAACCAUAAAACUCUUAGGAUGUGGCAGUGGUUUCUUGGAUAUGACACCAAAUUCACAGACAACGAAAGAAAAAAUAGGCAAAUUAUACUUCAUUAAAAUUUUGUGCAUCAAAGAACACUAUCAACAGAGUAAAAAGAUUACCUAUGGAGUGGGAGGAAAUAAUAUGCAGUUCACGUACCUAAUAAGGAUUAAACAUCCAGAAUACAUACAAAACUCCCAAAAUGCAACAACAGUGUAAAAACCUGAUUUAAAAAAUGGCAAAGGAUUUGGAUAGAUCUCCAGAGAGGACAUGCAGAUAGCCAGUGAGCACAGGAAAAAAUGCUUAGCAUCACUAAACAGUAAGGAAAUGCAAAUCAAAACCACAUUGAGAUACCACUUCAUACCCACUGGGAUAGCUCUUAUUAAAAUUAAAAAAACACACAAGUGUUGGCAAGGAUGUGGAGAAAUUGGAACUCUUAUUACUGAUGGAAAUAUAGUGGUAUGCAGCUGCUGUAGAAAACAGUAUGGUGAUUUUCCAAUUAAAUAUAGAAUUGUCAUUUGAUUCAGCAAUUGCAUUUCUGGGUAUAUACACAAAAUAAUUGAAAGCGGAGGCUUGAGGGUAUAUUUGUAUACCAGUGUUCACUGCAGCAUUAUUCACCGUAGUCAAAAGGUAGAAACAACCCAAAUACCCAACAGAUGAAUGGAUAGACAAAAUGUGUUAUAUCCAUACAAUGGAAUAUUAUUCAGCCAUAAAAAGGAAAUCCUUCUACAUACUACAUCAUGGAUGAACCUUUCAGACAUUAAGUAAAUCACAAAAGGACAAUACUAUAUGAAUCCACUGAUGUGAGGUACCUAGACUAGUGAGAUUCAUAGAGACAAAGUAGAACAAAGAUUACGUUUUGUCACAGGGAGCAGGAGGGAAUGGGAAUUUAUUGUUUAAGGGGCACAGAGAUUAGUGUGGGAUCAUGAAAAAGUUCCGGAGGUGCAUAGUGGUGACUGGUACAUACAACGAAUGUAUUUAAUGCCUUUAAACUGUAACUUCAAAAUGGUUAAAAUUUAAAUCUUACGUACAUUUUGCCACAGUAAAUUUUUAAACCACCAAAAAAAAAAAAAAAAAAAAAUAUGGCCUAGCUUUUUUUUUUUUUUUUAAAAAGGGCAGGGGGUGGGGUAUUUAGUCACAAGACAUAGAGGAACUUUAAGUGUAUAUUGCUAAGUGAAAGAAGUUAGUCUGAAAGGCUACAUACUACAUGAUUUCAAAUAUAUGACAUUCUGGAGAAAGCAAAGUUAGUAAAGACUGGUUGCCAGAGGUUCAGUGGGAGAGAGGGAGGGGUAAAUACAUGGAGUAGAGAUUUUUAGGGUGGUGAAACUACUGUAUACAAUACUAUAAUAGUGGAUACAUGACAUUAUAUAUUGGUCAAAAUCCAUAAAGACAUACAACAAAAAGAGGACCCUUCAUGUAAAUUACAGGCUUCAGCUAGCCUGGAUGACAGAGUGAGACUUUGUCUCAAAAAGUAAAGUAAAAAUGUGUCAAUAUUGGUUAAACAAAUAUACCACACUAGUGCAAGAUGUUAAUAAUAAAGGCCUGGGGUGGGGGGAAGCAUAGGGGAACUCUAUACUAUCUGCUCAGUUUUUCUGAAAAUCUAAAACUUCUAAUAAAGUCUAUUAAAAUUA